UUAGUCACAUCUGGUGGAACUGCAAAUUGUUUCAGUAUUGCUUAUCUCAAGGCCAGUGUUUGUUUAGCUGCUAGAGAAAAAGAAAAGCCUUGUGGCAGUGAGAACAGGUUCAUUCUUUAAGUGUGGGGUGACUGACUUAACCCUUGCCUGGCAUGGCCUUAGGUUCUGUUUAUAAUUUAGCGUCUUAUUUGCCACAAAGAGUCGGUCAUGUCAGUCUUACUAUCUCUAUUUUGUCUAUCUCUAUUUUAACAGUAAUGCUGGUCAGUUGUUGUGUCUGAAGCACAAAAAGGAGGAGGUAUAACGAGGCUUCUGACCUCCUGUCCUGUCGUGGCUGGAAGCUCAGUUUUAAAGUUUUUCUGGGGUCCCCUUGGCCAUAAAGGGGUCCAUUCAGUUUGGCAGGGGCUUAUAAUUUUAUUUUUAGUUUACACUUAAUAUUUUUCUUAGAAUCAGUUCUCUUUUUAAAUGUAUAUAAAUGUAUUUUAAGAAAGAAAGUUUGUAUGCUCGAAUUUAAUUGAGAAACCAGUCUCACCUGUCAUACACACAAACUAACAUCACAAUAAGUUCAUAGCAAAUAAAGCAUCAUCAUUCAUUUCUGACCAGAUACAGCCACUGAGCUGAAGGGCCAGACAGCAAGGCUGAGAGGCAGGUCGAAGUCCCAUGGUUAGGGCUUUCAGCUGGGGAGGGGUAUCUUUGUGCCAAGCUAGACUGUGUUUAAUCCUUUUAAUCACAAGAGACAAAAAUCCUCAGACACGAGAAGGCAUGUAUCACCUGAAAUUGCCUGAGAGGCUCAACCAACUUUUAGUCACAAGAUCUGCGAACACUUCCCUAGUGGGUGCUGAGGUUCUCCAAGGAGCUGCUGGGCCCAUUUGCAAACAGAUAAGCAAACGGCUGGCGGCCACCUCAGCUGUAUCCCAUAGAGUUGCCACCCAGGCCUCAGCCAGGACCUUUCAGGCCAGACAGGAGCACCUGACCAAAGGCUUCACAGCCGCCCUCACCGCCCGGCCUUCUACGGUGUCCAGAGACAGUUAGCCAGGCCUGGGCUGGGCACACUCCACCUUCCCUAGUCACCAGCUGGUUUCCCAGAGGAGAAGGCUGAGACCCGAGA